AGAGGUAUUGUGGCCAGUAUUUUGGUUUUCUUAUGUUUUGGAGUCACACAAGCUAAAGACGGGCCAUUUUCCAGACCUCAUCCAGCUUACUGGAGGUUUUGGCUCUGCGUGAGUGUGGUCUACGAGCUGUUUCUCAUCUUUAUACUCUUCCAGUUGCCACCACUAACUGUAGCCCCGCUGACGGGGGCACUGGCCUUGCAGACUGUCCAGGACGGCCGGCAGUUUCUAAAGUAUGUUGACCCCAAGCUGGGAGUCCCACUGCCAGAGAGAGACUACGGGGGAAACUGCCUCAUCUACGACCCAGACAAUGAGACUGACCCCUUUCACAACAUCUGGGACAAGUUGGAUGGCUUUGUUCCCGCGCACUUUCUUGGCUGGUACCUGAAGACCCUGAUGAUCCGAGACUGGUGGAUGUGCAUGAUCAUCAGCGUGAUGUUCGAGUUCCUGGAGUACAGCCUGGAGCACCAGCUGCCCAACUUCAGCGAGUGCUGGUGGGAUCACUGGAUCAUGGACGUGCUCGUCUGCAACGGGCUGGGCAUCUACUGCGGCAUGAAGACCCUUGAGUGGCUGUCCCUGAAGACGUACAAGUGGCAGGGCCUCUGGAACAUUCCGACCUACAAGGGCAAGAUGAAGAGGAUCGCCUUCCAGUUCACGCCGUACAGCUGGGUUCGCUUCGAGUGGAAGCCGGCCUCCAGCCUGCGUCGCUGGCUGGCCGUGUGCGGCAUCAUCCUGGUGUUCCUGUUGGCAGAACUGAACACGUUCUACCUGAAGUUUGUGCUGUGGAUGCCCCCGGAGCACUACCUGGUCCUCCUGCGGCUCGUCUUCUUCGUGAACGUGGGUGGCGUGGCCAUGCGUGAGAUCUACGACUUCAUGGAUGACCCGAAGCCCCACAAGAAGCUGGGCCCGCAGGCCUGGCUGGUGGCGGCCAUCACGGCCACGGAGCUGCUCAUCGUGGUGAAGUACGACCCCCACACGCUCACCCUGUCCCUGCCCUUCUACAUCUCCCAGUGCUGGACCCUCGGCUCCGUCCUGGCGCUCACCUGGACCGUCUGGCGCUUCUUCCUGCGGGACAUCACAUUGAGGUACAAGGAGACCCGGUGGCAGAAGUGGCAGAACAAGGAUGACCAGGGCAGCACCGUCGGCAACGGGGACCAGCACCCACUGGGGCUGGACGAAGACCUGCUGGGGCCUGGGGUGGCCGAGGGCGAGGGAGCACCAACUCCAAACUGACCUGGGCCGUGGCUGCCUCGUGAGCCUCCCAGAGCCCAGGCCUCCGUGGCCUCCUCCUGUGUGAGUCCCACCAGGAGCCACGUGCCCGGCCUUGCCCUCAAGGUUUUUUGCUUUUCUCCUGUGCACCUGGCGAGGCUGAAGGCGAGGGGUGGAGGAGGCCCCAGCACAGCCUCAUCUCCAUGUGUACACGUGUGUACGUGUGUAUGCGUGUGUGUACGCGUGUGUACGCGCGUGUGUACACAUGCGUGGCCGCCUGUGGUGUGCACGUGUGCUCUGGGCUCCGAGGCUUCUCCAGAGCUGGGAGCUGGCUGGCGUGGCAAGGGCAUGCUCUGGGGCAGUGUGUCCCUCAGGAACCAGGGUCCUCCCUCCCCUUUCUGCCUGGUCAGCCCCGUGGCCUCUGGCCCACCAAGCUCCCUGUCACCCAGCCAUGGUGUGGUCCAGGCAGGGACAUCUCGGUACCCUUUCUGCACUCCGUGGGCCCUGGGUGCGCUGAGGCCUGGAGGCGUCUACACUGGCUCCACAUCCACUUCCCCCGCAGCUCGUGUGGGCGCUCGUCCACAAACACUCCGUGGCUGAGAGGCAGCGGAUCCAGGCAGCGAUGCUGAGCCACCUCCUCCGAGCCUUCCUUUCACACAGACCACCCCGGAGGACACGUGGAUGAUGGGGUCAGAGAUCACUGAGCUGCCCCUCAAGGGGGCCUGGAACCCGGGUGCUGGGGUCAUGCUGCCUCCGUGGCUCCAAGGUGAGGGUCAUCUUCACGAGCAAAGAGAACCAAUAAAGUGACAACGAACGUCUGAGGCUUCCAGCCCUCCCCCCA